AACACUCAGGUGAGAACUUCUCAGGUGGAAAGCAGGAAGAGGGUGGCUAGUGCAAGGAUCAGAUAGCACCUGCUUGGAAGUUCACUGAUUAAUGAUUUAACAAGGGCGGUCACAUGGGACAACUGCUGCUUUUCUCUGCCCUCAUUUUUCUUACUAACAGGUCUGAAAAUUGAACAAGAUGGACGGGUCCAGGAAAGAGGAGGAGGAAGACAGCACAUUCACCAACAUUUCUCUUGCAGAUGACAUAGCUUGUUCAAUGUGAAAAUGAAGAAGAUGAAGACUUUCAUGAUGACCCACUUCCACGUAAUACCAUUCCUCAAGAAUUUUGUAUCCAAGGCCCAAAAGUUUGUUACCCAAGAUGAUGAAUGCUGACAUGGAUGCAGUUGAUGCUGAAAAUCAAGUGGAACUGGAGGAAAAAACAAGACUUAUUAAUCAAGUGUUGGAACUCCAACACACACUUGAAGAUCUCUCUGCAAGAGUAGAUGCAGUUAAGGAAGAAAAUCUGAAGCUAAAAUCAGAAAACCAAGUUCUUGGACAAUAUAUAGAAAAUCUCAUGUCAGCUUCUAGUGUUUUUCAAACAACUGACACAAAAAGCAAAAGAAAGUAAGGGAUUGACACCCUUCUGUUUUAUGGAAUUGCUGCUGAUCAUUUUUUCUUUAAAACUUGGAUAGAUUCCAAAAGUUACAGUACCUUUGUGGCUUCAUUGAAUAUUUAUGAAGAUAAUGUCAGAUGUAGACAAAAAUAACACAAUAACAGGAGACUUCCAUAAGUUUGUGUAUUAUGUUAGUCUAUGAAAACGUGCAAAUGUAUUGUAGAGACUUUAUGAUUAGAAUUGCAUAUAUUUAUGAAACUUAAAGAUGAAUGUUUUAUUGAAUUUGUAGGUUUAGCACUGUCUUUUAUUAUAGGAUUAGUAAGAUAUACAAGAAAAUAACCACCGUGUUGUGAAAAAGUGACCAAAAUCAUGUACUAAAUGCACAGCUUUAUGUACCCUGUCCACCAUCUUGUGCCUCUUCUCCAUUUGCCUCUUCCUUCCUAUUUCCCUUCCGCUAAGGAAAAAAAUUGGUGUCACAUUUGUAAAAGUAAUUUUAAUAGUUAAUCAUCUCUGAGAGUAACCUGUAUUUUAAUUGUUGAAACUUAACCAAAAUAAGAUACUGUCUCAGCUAGGGCUUGUCAUUUGUGUAUUUAGUGUUAAGAUAGGAAUGCUAGUGUCUCUUUAAUUAAUUGGAAAUAGAUGGAGGCUAAAAAUGAAGGUUUUUCUUUGAAACUGAAUUAACUUGGGAAUAUUUGUUGUUAAAAACUUCUUUUUGCCCAAAAUAACUCAUUUUGUAUUAUCUGAAAAUAUAUAAUUUCUGGUCAUGUGUAUGUUAAAAUAGAAAAUUUUGAGGAAAAAUGGAAAUAGGGUGGAAAAGUACUCGGUAAACAGUAGUAACCAAAUAUUUUCACUCCAGAUUUGUGUUUUCUCUGGCACAGAGUAGAUCUUUUGGGAAAUAUAUAUGAAAGUGGAUUAAGUUUGACUACCCUUAUGUUAGCCACAUCUGGAUGAGAACAGUUACAAAGAGUUUGGUCUCUAAGUUGAUUUGUACCCAGUGGGUCAACUUCUGCAAAAUUCCGUAAUGGUGUAUUAGUAUUAGAAUAGUGAAUAAAAUGGGAAAGUUAUACAUGUAUACUUAUUAUCUUGCUCAGUAUUUUAUCUCACUUGUUCUAGAAUUUUCUGUAAACCCUGCUACUGGGUUUGAAGAGUUUUAGUCAUCCUUUAACAAUUUUUAAAAAUUUAGCUUCUAGAUUCCAUUUGGUAAGGAAAUCAAUAUUGGAAGUAUUGCUAAAAUCUUAUAAUAUGAAAAGAGAUCCACUAAUGUAGCUUAAGGUUAUUAGAUUUGGGCUUUUAAUCAUGGAAUAAUCUUAUGUAUUGGUGUAAGAGUUGAUGAAUGACUUUAGCUGUGUGAAUAUAUAAUAGUCAAACUGCAAACAUUUUGCAUCCCUUUUGUGACCUAAUUUACAGACAUUUAAAUUGUGUUGCAGUUCUGCUUUGCCGUUUAAUAAAAAGCUAUUUCAGAGGUUGUGUGUGUUUUGAUAUAGUUGCCUAAGUAAAUGGGGUAUUUAGGUAUAGUGGUGUAUCCAGGGUUAUUCAAUGCCACAGAAUAGUGUAUCUUAUUUAAGUACCCAGUUACUGAUUAUUUAGGGGAAUAAUAUUUUUAUUAAUACAACUAUAACUGGUUAUCAAUAUAAAUAUCAUAGGCUAUUAUACAUUAAUUUGGAAAACAAAAGCAAAGCACUCAAAGGAUCCAGUAUCUCCAGGGAAAAAGGAAGUUGUAUUUUUUAGGGUAGGCUAAGCUACUUUAGCAAGAGACCCAGUGAUAAAGAAUAUAAAUAUAGAAGUUUCUCUCCCAACCAGUGGUUCCAAGGUCAGCAUUGCAGGCUAGCAGCCCUUGUUCAAACAGUUAUUCAGGGACUUUGGCUGAGGAUGGUGCUGCCAUUUUAAAUCAUGGCUUUCAAGUCACUCUAGUUAUUCUUCUAAUUUGCAGAAAAAGAACAUGGAAGUGUACAUAUGCAAGGUGUUAUGGGCUGUGCCUGGAAAUGGCUCAUAUAUCUUCUCAUAUUCCAGUGGUGUGGAGACUUAGUUACAUCUAGAUACAAGAGGAGCUGAGAAAUGUAGUCCCUGGCUGGGAAGCCAUCUUCCAGCUAUAAAUACAAGAUUUUGGUGGCUGCUAGCAGCCUCAGCCACAGCUCUUCUUGUGCUACCAAGUAUCUUCCCUUACACAGAAAGUAAUCCCUCUUCAUCCAGCUAGUGAUUCAGCUCACAAUCUAGGAUCUCUAUUAAAGGUCCAUCCCUUUACAUGUGGCUUCUAAUAGUCUGACAAUCUCUAAACUGAUAGGCAAAUUAUUUGCUCUCACCCUUGCUGCUGCCCAUUUAUAAUGUAGUUGGGACAGGAUGGCCAAAUAAAAAGUCUCAAUUUGGAAAAUGGAAUAAAGGGAAACGUAAAAAUUGUGGAAUGCUCCUGGGAGAUGUAUGAAGAUUUUGUCCCUAGCAGUGGAGAAGUUCCUUGAUUCAACUAUGAUUCUGAUCUCUGGCAGGGGACUCCCUUGUUCAUUGAACUCCAUGGUUUCCCCUCUGGAAAGUUACUCCUUAUCCAUUUUCUUCCAUGGCUACCUCAGAAGUAGAGAUUGGGUGUUCACUCCAUGGGAAUUGUGAAGACAGUCCACUUCCUGCUGGUGUGAAUUUGGUGCCCAUCAUUUUAAGGCCAAGCUCAUGUUUCUGUGGAAUACGAUUCUCUCAAAAACUCAAGCCUUUUUAUCAGUGUGCUUCUGAUUGCAUAUGCCGAGGAACCACAACCAAGCUUUUGACCAAAUUCUCAAAGUAUGUAUUAUUUUUGCCUUUCUUUAAUGGAGGCUAUCUUGAGAUCAACUAAAAAUAAGAUUACACUGGGAAUGUUACAUGCAGAUCAUCACUGCAAAGCUGGGUUCCUUUGGCUUAACGAUUGGUAGAGAAGUCUUCAUGGGCUUCCCCCCAAUCUCCCCCACCUCAAAAAUAAUUUUGAACCUUUGCUGCUAUUCAGACUUCAGAAACAAUUGGCUUAAUUUCAUGAGGUUCCUUGUAUCAAAACUUUGUCUAUUCCCUUCUAUCUUUGCUUGAAAAUGUCAAUUUUUUUGAUACCUUGCUGAAAGCAAGGAAUAGCCAAUUCACUUAACAUUCUGGCUUUUUCCAGCUAGAGCUAUCAGAUUAGUAGGUGUCAAAAUAUAUCCCCACUGCUUGUCAUGUUAAUGGUAAGCUAAUGCUAUAUACUUAGUUUUUGCUAUGCAAUACUUCAGGAUAAUUUCUUCAUUAGAAAUAUAGGUGGUACACAGUGUGCACAGGGACUGUGUCCAGCUUCUGGAAAAGACUCGACCAAAUUUUAGACAGGCACCUCUGAGCCCUGUUUUUGACUAGUCCAGUUUUAGCAAAAAUCCUGCUAAAUGAGUUUAGAGAUAAUCCCAUCCUCAAUAACUGAUGAUCGUCAACCUGGCCUGUCUUUGGCAAGAAUCACCCUACUCUUGAUGUCUCCAGUUAGUAGUUUUCCAUCCACUGACCUCAUCACUGCUCAUUGACUAUAAAUCCUCAGUUGUAUUUGCUGUGUUAGUUGAGCCCAGUUUCUUUCCCUUAUUGGGUGAUGGUCUUAACAUAUACAGUCCUGAGUAAAGUCUUCUUUACUGCUUUAACAAGUGUCAGAAUGGUUUUUCCUUUAAUACUUCCUAGUUUACAUGCUGGUAGAAUAAUGUUUGGUAGGGAAAAAUCAGCAUACUCCUUGUUAUGGACUGAAUGUGUCCUCCCAAAAUUCUUAGGUUGAAAUCCUAACCCCAAUGUGAUGCUUUUAGGAGGUGGGGCUUUUGGGAGAUAAUUAGGUAAUGAGGGUGAAACCCUCAUGAAUGGGAUUGUGUCAUUAAAAGAAACCCCAGAGAGCUCUCUUUCUGCCACAUAGAAGACAGCAGUCUGCAUCUUGGAAGAGGGCCCUCAACACUGAUCUCUCAGACUUCCAGCUUCCAAAACUGAGAAAUAAAUUUGUUUAUAAGCCACCCAGUCUAUAUUUUGUUAUAGCAUCCCAAAUAGUUUAAGGCACCCAUUUUCCCCACUGUUUCCCAAUACAAAUUUCCCCAGUAUUGACACUGCCAUUCUAUGCAAAAUGUGUCCUCUUUAUAGUCCCUUUGGACUCACAGCAGGUUACUACACAUCACAGAUCCUCGUCUGAAACUUGUAGGGCCAGAUGUCUUAGAAUUUGGAGUUUUCCAGAUUUUAUAAAAUAUUAUGACUCAGACACCAAUAUGGUUUGGGGCAACACCUAUAAUCAAGUAUAUUAACAUUUCUGUAGCAAAAUGAGUAUUAAAGUAGGAUAAAGAAAGACUACAUAUGUACAUAAAACCUUGCCGGGGAAGUCAGGCUCAGCUACCAGGUGAGUUUUGUUGCCAAAAUGCUAGGAAAAUCUUUAACUUUUCAGAGAUUUUUGGUCAUGGAAUUGUAGCAACAAAACCUUUUGUAGAAGAGUAACCAAAAUCAUGUAUGCAUUUAGUUCCAACUAGUUAAUGUCACAUCUCUAUUCCUGUCACCCUUCCCUGUGAUCUAGUCCCUUUUGUAAGAGAAAUAUGGUAGUUGAAUUAUAAAAUCUAAAAUUAAUUUUGUGGUCCAAAGAAAAGCAAAAUAGAUCUUUAGAAUGUAAAGCCAUUCUUUACUUUGCCCAAUAAAAAUUUUGUUAUUCCCUGAA